CUGGUGGUGGACCUGUGCCCCUGUUCGUAUUUCCCUGUCCCGGGGUGAGAGCAGGUUGGGGUCCUGUGGCACUCCAACCUCGGAUCCCAGGAGCUACCAACCUGCAGGUUCAUUCGUUGUAUUUACGGGCCGGAGGAAAGGCAGUGUAUAGAGUAGAGGUCGGGAGUAGCUCUGGCUUUGAACAACCCGUCCACUUUCUGUUGAACUCUGGGCUAGUUACUUAACCUCCUUAAAGGCUCAGUUGUGAAUUGGACCUUAGUCUCUCCUGUAGGUGGUCAUUUGAAGGAUAAAAGGACCUAGCACACAGUAUAAGCAAUCAAAUAUGCUCUUUAUAAGCUGGAGUCUUUGGCGUUGCUUGGAAGAUCUGAAUACAGUCUUAAAUCAGUUCCUGGCACACCCCGCAUAGUGUUGCCCCCGUCGGAGGCAGCUCUUAUGCUAAUGAAAGCCCGCAGAAUUCAGUGUCCUGUGAUUUAUAGUUUGGACGUCACAUUCGAAACCAUUGUCUUUCUCUGUCCUCUGUAGAAGAAACAGUUUGUGUGAAGGCUGUAAGGCUUGGAGAGGUUUUGGCUAUUUUGACGACUAGAAGGUGGGCCAUAUGAGUGUGACUGAAGUUUAGUGGAAGACAUAUGGUGUGGAAUGACCCAGAAGGACUACAUCACAGCAAGCUCAUUUGAUAUAGUCAUCGUUGGUGGCGGAAUUGUGGGGCUUGCCUCUGCCAGAGCACUCAUCCUGCGACAUCCAUCACUUUCUAUUGGUGUUCUGGAAAAGGAGAAAGAUUUAGCUGUUCACCAGACUGGACAUAACAGUGGUGUCAUACAUAGUGGAAUUUAUUAUAAACCUGAGUCUCUGAAAGCCAAAUUAUGUGUACAAGGUGCAGCCCUCCUCUAUGAGUACUGUCAGCAAAAGGGAAUUUCCUACAAGCAGUGUGGCAAGCUUAUAGUAGCUGUUGAACAAGAAGAAAUUCCCAGACUUCAGGCCCUAUAUGAGAAAGGCCUCCAGAAUGGUGUCCCGGGCCUGAGGCUGAUCCAGCAGGAGGAUAUAAAAAAGAAGGAGCCAUAUUGUAGGGGUCUAAUGGCUAUUGAUUGUCCACAUACUGGCAUUGUGGACUAUCGGCAGGUGGCUUUGUCAUUUGCCCAGGAUUUCCAAGAAGCAGGUGGCUCUGUCUUGACCAAUUUUGAAGUAAAAGGUAUUGAAAUGGCUAAAGAAAGUCCUUCAAGAAGUAUAGAUGGAAUGCAAUAUCCAAUUGUUAUAAAGAAUACAAAGGGAGAGGAAAUUCGAUGUCAGUAUGUUGUGACAUGUGCAGGACUUUACUCAGACCGUAUUUCAGAGUUGAGUGGCUGCACUCCUGAUCCUCGAAUUGUACCAUUCCGGGGAGAUUACCUGCUUUUGAAGCCAGAAAAAUGUUAUCUUGUAAAAGGAAAUAUUUAUCCGGUCCCAGAUAGCCGGUUUCCUUUCCUAGGAGUUCACUUCACACCAAGGAUGGAUGGCAGUAUUUGGCUAGGGCCUAAUGCAGUUCUUGCCUUUAAACGAGAGGGUUACAGACCCUUUGACUUCAGUGCCACAGAUGUUAUGGAUAUAAUUAUCAAUAGUGGCUUGAUUAAACUGGCAUCCCAGAAUUUUUCCUAUGGAGUUACUGAAAUGUAUAAAGCAUGUUUUCUUGGUGCAACAGUGAAGUAUCUUCAAAAAUUCAUCCCUGAAAUUACUAUCAGUGAUAUACUUAGGGGCCCAGCUGGAGUAAGAGCCCAGGCCCUGGAUAGAGAUGGAAAUCUGGUAGAAGAUUUUGUAUUUGAUGCAGGAGUUGGGGAUAUUGGAAAUCGCAUUCUUCAUGUGAGAAAUGCACCUUCUCCUGCUGCUACUUCUUCCAUUGCAAUUUCUGGAAUGAUUGCAGAUGAAGUACAACAAAGAUUUGAAUUAUAAAUAAUGAAAGGAGCUAGGUAUGCACUGUAAUCUUCAUGUCAGCAACAAGAAUGUACUAAUUGCAUUCUUUAAUUUAAAAAAUGGUUUUUAAACUUUAGUUUUUAGGUCAAAGAUAACCACUGCAUUGUUAAAAUGAUGUAACAUAGAAAUAAUAAUUUUCUACAAAAAUUAGCCAGGCAUGGUGGCGCAUGCCUGUAAUCUCAGCUACUCAGGAGGCUGAGGCAGGAGAAUCAAUUGAACCGAGCAGACGGAGGUGAGCUGAGAGCUGAGAUUGCACCACUGCACUCCAGCCUGGGUGACAGAGCAAGAAAAUAAUAAUAAUAAUAAUUUUCAAAAUGUUAGGCUGGGGGCCGUGGCCAGCACUUUGGGAAGCCAAGGCAGGUAGAUUGUAGCCCAGGAGUUUGAGAACAGCCUGGGCAACAUGGCAAAACCCUGUUUCUACACAAAGUUAGCUGGGUCUGGUGCCUCUGUAGUUCCAGCUCCUCAGUAGGCUGAGGUGAGAGGAUCACUUGAGCCCAGGAGGUCUAGGCUGCAGUGAGCUUAUGUUCAUGACACUGCAUUCCAGGCUGGAUGAUAGAGCAAGAUCUUGUCUCAAAAAAAAAAAAAAAAAAAAAAAAAAUCCAGCCUGGGCAACAUAGUGAAUGAAACCCCAUCUCUACAAAAAAUACAAAAAUUAGCUGGGCAUGAUGGUGUGUGCCUGUAGUCCCAGCUACUUGGGGGCUGAGGCAGGAGGAUCGCUUGAGCCCGGGAGAUCAAGGCUACAGUGAGCUGUGUUCAUGCCACUAUACCCCAGCCUGGGCAACAAAGUGAGUCCCUGACUCAAAAAAUAAAAACAACAACAAAAAAUAAAUUCCAUGCUUAUUUACUUUGCGAAUAAAGAGGCAAGGUACAGUUUUAUCUGUCCGAAUCCCUGACUUUUAUUUAUUUUUUUUUUCAGACGGAGUUUCACUCUUGUUGCCCAGGCUUGAGUGCAAUGGUACGAUCUUGGCUCACUGCAACCUCUGCCUCCCGGGUUCCAGCGAUUCUCUUGCCUCAACCUCCUGAGUAGCUGGGAUUACAGGCGCCCACCACCAUGCCUGGCUAAUUUUUUGUAUUUUUAGUAGAGACGGGGUUUUGCCAUGUUGGCCAGGCUGGUCUCGAAUUCCUGACCUCAGGUGAUCCACCUGCCUCAGCCUCCCAAAAUGCUGGGAUUACAGGUGCGAGCCAUCAUGCUCAGCCCUGAAUCCCUGACUUUGUUAAUGACCUGUCCUUACCAACCAUGACCUAGAGAAGAUUUGGCUUUUUAAGAGUUUUGGAGAAAGAUGGCAUAAAAAUAGAUUAUUUCCUUAAAUCAAUUUUUUAGCAUUACGCUACCUAAGCUCGUUUGGUCUCUCAUAGACAAGAAAAUACAUUAUAUUGUAGGUUACAUUCUUUUAAUUUUGAAGAGUCACAAAACUCACAUUAUUUAGAGCAACAAUAUUUGUAUUUGGAAAUUAAAAAUUCAUGAUUUCAAGAAAAUACAUAAAAUUUACAUUUUUGAGUAGUUUGAAUAAGUUUCUAUCUUAAUUAUAAUAUUUGUAGGAAAUAACAAAACAAACUCAAAGCCUUUAUUAUUUCCAGUCUCUUUGUAACUGAUGUGGUAUGGUAUCAUCAUGAAAUCUAAACAGUGGUACACUGAGUGGUUGUCCUGUUCUUCAAUCUCUGUGGCUGAGAACUGAAAUAACUUAGAAGAGACAGAUUUUUAUGAGAGCAGUUUUAGAAUCCUGACACUGAUGUAUAGAACUCCAAUUUAAAAAAGUUAUUUAUCUAUUAUAUCUCUGAUCUUUAGUCACACUAAGGCUCUCAAAAUGUUGGCCAAGAUUGGUAAUGAUUCAUACGUACUUGAUUUUUCAGGGCUCCUAUAAACUUGUAUAGGGAUAUUUUUCCAUUUUUGAUAAAUAUCUAACUUUGAGGCAUUCACUUUUGUAAACCGCGAAAGUGCCUUACAUUCACCUCAUGAGUAUUUUAAGUUGAUGCCCAGUGCUGUGGUAUAUCCUGUAUAUAUGUGUUUUGUGGUAUCUAUCGAAAUUAUUCUUAUAAUUUAGAAAGUUAGAAAAUAGAAAUUGUAAAUGAAAAUGUGGCGACCUGACUGCAGAACUUUGAGUACUGAACCACAUUUAGGUGAGGCAUUUUCAUCCAUUCUCUCUGAUUUGCUCUCUCAGGAUUCAUCUUCUACUGUGUAUGUCUUCUUUCCUCUUAGCUCUCCAAAGCUGUAUGAUGGAUGGGUGAGAAGGAUGUGCAUUUUGGUUGAUAGGAAAAAUGUUUCUGUUUUCUUCCUUUUCCCCUCACUUCAAGCAUUGAUGAUUACAUUGAUUGAGCUACCUCAUCCAUUAAUUUGAAAGGCUACACUUCAUCAGCUCAUGUUUAAGAAGUAGCACAUCCCAGGUAAACAGAGUAGGCCAUUAUUCAACUCUUAGGAUGAGUAUAUUAAAAGCAUUCAGAUAUCAAUGACAGAAGAAACAAGCCCUAAUGUUUCUUUAUAACAGCUGAUUCCUGCAAGAAAUGCAAACACAGGAUAUUUUUCUGUUCCAUUACAAGAUUACUAAGAGAUGGAAAAUAUUAUCAUUCUGUAUUUUGUCAGUAGUACGAUUGCAUACAUACUAAGUUGUAAACAUUGAAUUACAAAAAAUGAUUGUCCUAAUUGAAGCAGUCCUCAAUCCAUUUGAGUCUGUACAAUACCCUGAAAAGGAAACAACAGGUGCUGGAGAGGAUGUGGAGAAAUAGGAACACUUUUACACUGUUGGUGGGACUGUAAACUAGUUCAACCAUUGUGGAAGUCAGUGUGGCGAUUCCUCAGGGAUCUGGAACUAGAAAUACCAUUUGACCCAGCCAUCCCAUUACUGGGUAUAUACCCAAGGGACUAUAAAUCAUGCUGCUAUAAAGACACAUGCACACGUAUGUUUAUUGUGGCACUAUUCACAAUAGUAAAGACUUGGAACCAACCCAAAUGUCCAACAACGAUAGACUGGAUUAAGAAAAUGUGGCACAUAUACACCAUGGAAUACUAUGCAGCCAUAAAAAAUGAUGAGUUCAUGUCCUUUGUAGGGACAUGGAUGAAAUUGGAAAUCAUCAUUCUCAGUAAACUAUCGCAAGAACAAAAAACCAAACACCGCAUGUUCUCACUCAUAGAUGGGAAUUGAACAAUGAGAACACAUGGACACAGGAAGGGGAACAUCACACUCUGGGGACUGUUGUGGGGUGGGGGGAGGGGGGAGGGAUAGCAUUAGGAGAUAUACCUAAUGCUAAAUGACGAGUUAAUGGGUGCAGCACACCAGCACGGCACAUGUAUACAUAUGUAACUAACCUGCACAUUGUGCACAUGUACCCUAAAACUUAAAGUAUAAUAAUAAACAAUAUAUAUAUAUAUAUAUAUAUAAAAUACCCUGAAAAAUAAAAAUGAAAAAUUUGUUGAAAGUGUUUUGAAUAUGUAGGUUAUUCUGCUUGUAAAACGUUUUAUAUGUAUGUCAAUAGGGUUUUUUUGUUUAAUACUGAUAUAAUAAAGUUUUAUGUAUUUCUGACAGAAGAAAUGUAUAUUAAUAUUUAAAAUAUUUUAAUGAGCCUUGGUGUUGUAGAGAACAUAUUUUUUAGUUCCAUAAAAACUUUUAUGCAAAUAAAUUUUUUUAUGUGUAAAACAUAAACUGUUUGCUUUAGAUAGAUAGCAGCCAACCUUUUUAAAAAACUCAUUUCUGUGUUAGUAUAUAAUACAAAAUGAGGUUGAGUCAUUUAUAUUUUGGGUAAAAAGUGGAGCAUUUUAGAUUUUAACUUCAGAGUGUUUGUGAGGAACUCUUGAUGUACCAGCAAGUAUAUUUUUGGUGUUUCAUGUUACGUAGCUUAACUCUUUUAUCCAUACAUAUAUGUGUAUAUCAAAGUCCUUCCCUUGAUCCUCUCAGCAUUAGCACUGUUUGGGGAGUUGCCUUUACUGUUGGCAGAAUUCCACUUUCCCUGAGGCCAUUUGGAAAUCUACCUAGUAGCCUGUGGGAUAACCUUAACUCUUAGAACUUUCUUCAAAGGAUGGUGGUGAGAAUGGGGUAUACUGCCAGGCCCUGGCCUACGGGAGUUUGUAGGGCCUACUUUUGGAGGCAAUCCAACCCUGAUGGCUGUACCUAUGAGCUAUCCCUGUAAACACAGGAGACAUGGUGUCUAUAUUGUUUAAGGACUGGCUCUGCCCUCCUGGGCCCUUAAUCUGUGUCUAGACUUCUUGGUCAGAGGUUUCCUCAUCUUUCUGCGCAUACACUAUUAUCUAAAGAUCUUGUAAACAUUUUUGAGUUGUAAUCGUAAAGUCAGUUUCUAAGCUUUUCUAACACACUCAAAGGGAGUUUUUGAAAUCUCUUCAUCAGGGCUUAAGGUAGAAGGACAGGGUGAAAUGGUUGGGAAAGCAAAAGCUGCCUCGAGAUGUUUUCAAAUAGUUUGUACUCAUUAAAUAGCUUAAGAAUGGAAAUAAACCCUGAAGCCCUGAAGGGAAGAACAGUGUUGAUACCAACCAACUCUACUUUUCUGGCCUCAAAUCCUAGAAAGUAUUGUGGGUUUGUUGUUGUUGUUGAUGUUGUUAAUUGCUUGUAUUUUCUGCUUAUGGGAAGGAUCUCACAUUAAAGUUAUCUUAUUUUAA